CCUAUUCUGAUCAGGUAGAUUUGCCUACAGAACACUGGGAGUUAUAUUGUUGAAAGAAUGCUUGAUGGAAUGUUUUGUGUACGAUAUCAGUUUCAUGUUUUAAUGCUUCCCCACUUAGUUGUAAUAGAGUCUGUGGAACAAAAAUGAAACAUUCUUGUUGAACUUAAGGUUAGAAUGAUUAUAUAACCUGAGAUUGUGUUAAAGAUAUUCAAAGUUGUGUUCUGUUUUGUUUUUUGAGGAAAGAUACAGCCUGGGAAUUUUAAAAACUUCUUUUAGCACUAUUUAAGUAUUUUUGCUUCUUCUAAAAAAGUGUAAUUUUAAAAAUAAACAUUUAAAUUAUUUAGGGGAUGAUUAUUUUAGGUCUUAGUGUAGUUAAAUAUUUCUUCUGGAACAUAUAAUGUAAUUCAGUUUUUGAAGCAAAAAUAAUUAGUAUUUUAGAACAGAAGUUUCAGUUUUUAAUGAUAAAUUCCCUUGUCAGUGUCUUUUAUAUUUCUGACUUUAGCUGAGAUGUAAUUUCAUGAAAUUAUUUGAACACCAUAUUGAUUAAAUUCAUUCUUUACACAAUCUGUUCUAAUUUUAUUUUGAUGCUGAUUUCUCUGCCUGGUUCAAGGAAUGAGCUUAAAGCAAUGUAUAACAUAUGUGAAUUUUCUAGUACUCUAUGAAAAUUUACCAAGACUGAAAUGUAUUUUUGUAGCUGUACUUCAUGAAAGCUGGGACAGGUGGUUUAAAACAAAAACCUAAAAAUUAAAUAAAAAAUCACUAUGAUAAUAUAAUAGAAACUUUAGUUUGGGAAUGUUCGGUUAUCAAAUCUACACCAGAUAAAACUAUUGUAGCUAUACCAUUUACUUGAGUUCCAUUGGAGCUUAAAUUCUGGCACUGCCUUAAGUAGUAUAGAAAUGAAAAACAGGAUAUGUGUUAUUACAUAGUACCCAGAGAUACUGUAACUUCAGUUAUAAUUUAACAUAUUCCCCUAUGUUCACAGUUUGUGGCAUAUAAUUCUUAGAGUUACAGUGAAAAAUUUAGAAUAUAUUAUUCUCUAAUAUUAAAACUUAAUAUUUAAUAGAAAUUUCCUUCAAUUUUUGAACAAAAGAAAAUAUUUUAAUAUGGUUACAUAAUAUAUCACACUGAUUGUGUGAAGACCAAAUUGAGCUCUGUUUUUAAGGUAAGAUUUCACCUGAAUCUUUUUCAGGUUUAUGUUAGUACAUCAAACUUUCUAACUUCAAAGGGAUUUUAAGAUUGUAUUGAGAUACUAACAUUCAAUUGAAAAAAUGAAUACUGCUGUUCUUCCACCGCGGGGAUACUUAAGAAUCACUGUCUGUGAGCCACAAUGUUUGAGGAUUUUUCUAGAUGAAUCUGUAAUGAUAAAUCUGGGCUUAUCCAACAUUUGUAUACCUAGUUCCCUUUUUAAUUGUUCCUUAUUCAUUGAUUCCUAUUCUUUGCCAGACACUCUACUAGGCACUGGUGGUGCAUAGAGAAGACACAUUUCCAAGACAGGCAACUUAGGGGAAUAGUCUGAGGCCACAUAGCUUUAAUCAUCUGAGUUCAUGCUGAAUAAAUCAAUCUAUUGGCAGGAUGUAUUGUACAGAGUGGCUGUGAAGAUAAUAUUAAAUAACAUGUAAAUUGCCUUGUAAAACUUAGCAAACAUGUGGGUACCUAUCUGAAUAUAUAUACAGGUGAUUUGUUUUUAGAUGUUGCUGUGCAUGGUGUUGACCACUCCUGUUUGAUUUAGAGAAACAGUAUAGUAUGGUAUUUAAAGCAUAGACUAGGAGCCAGAAUGCCUGGGUUUUGAUCUGACUCUAUGGUUUACAAGCUCUGUGACCUUGCCCAAGUUACUUAACCUUGCUGUACUUUAUUUUCCUCAUCUUCAAAAUGAGGAUGAUAACCAAGCCUACUUUAUGGGAUUGUUGUGAGAACCAAAUGAGUUAAUACAUGAAAAGCACUUAGAAUAGUGCUUAAUACAUACUAUGUGUUUAAUAAAUAUUAGCUAUUAUUAUUUUUAGUAUACUUAUAUUUGAUUUAUAACAGUUUUUUUAACACGGUACAGGUAAUAUAUGAACUUAAAUAUGGUUUCUUGUUUCAAAGUUUAUAGGCCUACUUUGUUCCUUGGGCCACAUGUUCCUUCCAGUCAUCGCUUGGGCUUGUUGAUACAUGUGAUGUGUGCCAGAUUUUUACACACUUACUAGAACUUGUGAAAUGAAUGUCAUCCUUUUCAAACUACUAUAAUUAUUUUUCUGAUUUUUUUUUUUUUUUUGAGACAAGGUCUCAGUCACUCAGGCUGGAGUGUAGUGACCCAAUCACAGGUUACUGCAGCACUUCAACCUCCCAUGCUCAACUGAUCCUCCUACUUCAGCCCCGCAAAGCACUUGGAUUACAGGCACCUGCUGCCACACACACCUGGCUAAUUUUAUUUGUAUUUAUUUGUAGAAAUGGGGUCUCCUUAUGUUGCGCAGGCUGGUCUCAAACUACUGGACUCAAGCGAUCCUCCUGCCUCAGCCUCUUAAGGUGUUGGGAUUACAGGAUGAGCUGCCAUGCCUGGCCUCAAACUACUCAUGUUUAGAACACUGUAUUUCCUGUUUAGGAAUCACUUUUAGGACAUAUGGCAUAUUGUUUUAAACAUCCUUUUUGGUGGUAUAUCUCUUCUUUGAGAGUAGGUUUGAUUUAAUUAAAUAAUAUAUUUUUUCAUGUUUUAGAAAGGUGAGUGAUAAGAAGUAUAAUUUGAAUUAAAAUGAAAAAUGGAGUAUAAAGUAAAAUGAAUAUUUUAAAAAUAUCUAAACAUAAUUAGAAAAGAAGAUUCCAAAAAUAUUUUUGAUAACUUGUCCUUGUUUACCCUUCUGAAGUGUCUAUUUAGAAAGGUGACACUGUCAGAUAUAUAAAUUGUAGUUUGUUAAAAUGUACAUGUUCACAGUCUCACACAGAAUUAUUACUUAAUAUUUGUGAAUCUUAUGUUGCUAUGCUUCUGAGGCUAAGUACUGUGUAAUAUAACCUAAAAUUCUUUAGAAAGUGUUUGUGGUCACAUUUCCUAGCUGAUAUUGUGCAUGCUUUUAAUAGCUUUUCUGUUAAAAAUUAUUUGGUAUUUCUCACAGAACUUUAAAUAUGCUCUAAUGUAUGUUAUGAAUUCCAAAGAUGAUAUGGUAUGUAUAAUUUUUCAUUUAUUAACUACAGAAUUCAUAACACAUCUCUUAGCAUCUCUUAUACCCAGUUCCCUUUUUUAACUAUAUAAAAUGAGUCAUUACAUUAUAUGUUUUACAUGUCAUUUUGUCUUCACAGCUAUUCUCUGCAAUAUAUCCUGCCAAUAAAUUGAUUUAUUCAGCAUGAACUCAGAUAAUUAGCAUCACUCAGAUGAUGCUAAUAAAGUACCUCGACCUAGUGGAUAUUUAAGAAACUGGAUUUACUCUUCAGGGAGACUAGUUCAUGGCCAUUAAGAUCAUUUGUAAGCCUAGCUGAUCCUGCUGCCCUUGGCUUCAUCAUUUCUCCAUGGUCUCUGCUGUUGCUGCCAUCUGGUAGUGUGUCAUUUACAGAUGAAAAUAUUUCCAAUCAGGAUCUUCGAGCAUUCACUGCACCAGAGGUUCUUCAAAAUCAGUCACUAACUUCUCUCUCAGAUGUUGAAAAGAUCCACAUUUAUUCUCUUGGAAUGACACUGUAUUGGGGGGCUGAUUAUGAAGUGCCUCAGAGCCAACCUAUUAAGCUUGGAGAUCAUCUCAACAGCAUACUGCUUGGAAUGUGUGAGGAUGUUAUUUACGCUCGAGUUUCUGUUCGGACUGUGCUGGAUGCUUGCAGUGCCCACAUUAGGAAUAGCAAUUGUGCACCCUCAUUUUCCUACGUGAAACACUUGGUAAAACUGGUUCUGGGAAAUCUUUCUGGGACAGAUCAGCUUUCCUGUAACAGUGAACAAAAGCCUGAUCGAAGCCAGGCUAUUCGAGAUCGAUUGCGAGGAAAAGGAUUACCAACAGGAAGAAGCUCUACUUCUGAUGUACUAGACAUACAAAAGCCUCCACUCUCUCAUCAGACCUUUCUUAACAAAGGGCUUAGUAAAUCUAUGGGAUUUCUGUCCAUCAAAGAUACACAAGAUGAGAAUUAUUUCAAGGACAUUUUAUCAGAUAAUUCUGGACGUGAAGAUUCUGAAAAUACAUUCUCCCCUUACCAGUUCAAAACUAGUGGCCCAGAAAAAAAACCCAUCCCUGGCAUUGAUGUGCUUUCUAAGAAGAAGAUCUGGGCUUCAUCCAUGGACUUGCUUUGUACAGCUGACAGAGACUUCUCUUCAGGAGAGACUGCCACAUAUCGUCGUUGUCACCCUGAGGCAGUAACAGUGCGGACUUCAACUACUCCUAGAAAAAAGGAGGCAAGAUACUCAGAUGGAAGUAUAGCCUUGGAUAUCUUUGGCCCUCAGAAAAUGGAUCCAAUAUAUCACACUCGAGAAUUGCCCACCUCCUCAGCAAUAUCAAGUGCUUUGGACCGAAUCCGAGAGAGACAAAAGAAACUUCAGGUUCUGAGGGAAGCCAUGAAUGUAGAAGAACCAGUUCGAAGAUACAAAACUUAUCAUGGUGAUGUCUUUAGUACCUCCAGUGAAAGUCCAUCUAUUAUUUCCUCUGAAUCAGAUUUCAGACAAGUGAGAAGAAGUGAAGCCUCAAAGAGGUUUGAAUCCAGCAGUGGUCUCCCAGGGGUAGAUGAAACCUUAAGUCAAGGCCAGUCACAGAGACCGAGCAGACAAUAUGAAACACCCUUUGAAGGCAACUUAAUUAAUCAAGAGAUCAUGCUAAAACGGCAAGAGGAAGAACUGAUGCAGCUACAAGCCAAAAUGGCCCUUAGACAGUCUCGGUUGAGCCUAUAUCCAGGAGACACAAUCAAAGCGUCCAUGCUUGACAUCACCAGGGAUCCGUUAAGAGAAAUUGCCCUAGAAACAGCCAUGACUCAAAGAAAACUGAGGAAUUUCUUUGGCCCUGAGUUUGUGAAAAUGACAAUUGAACCAUUUAUAUCUUUGGAUUUGCCACGGUCUAUUCUUACUAAGAAAGGGAAGAAUGAGGAUAACCGAAGGAAAGUAAACAUAAUGCUUCUGAACGGGCAAAGACUGGAACUGACCUGUGAUACCAAAACUAUAUGUAAAGAUGUGUUUGAUAUGGUUGUGGCACAUAUUGGCUUAGUAGAGCAUCAUUUGUUUGCUUUAGCUACCCUCAAAGAUAAUGAAUAUUUCUUUGUUGAUCCUGACUUAAAAUUAACCAAAGUGGCCCCAGAGGGAUGGAAAGAAGAACCAAAGAAAAAGACCAAAGCCACUGUUAAUUUUACUUUGUUUUUCAGAAUUAAAUUUUUUAUGGAUGAUGUUAGUCUAAUACAACAUACUCUGACGUGUCAUCAGUAUUACCUUCAGCUUCGAAAAGAUAUUUUGGAGGAAAGGAUGCACUGUGAUGAUGAGACUUCCUUAUUGCUGGCAUCCUUGGCUCUCCAGGCUGAGUAUGGAGAUUAUCAACCAGAGGUUCAUGGUGUGUCUUACUUUAGAAUGGAGCACUAUUUGCCCGCCAGAGUGAUGGAGAAACUUGAUUUAUCCUAUAUCAAAGAAGAGUUACCCAAAUUGCAUAAUACCUAUGUGGGAGCUUCUGAAAAAGAGACAGAGUUAGAAUUUUUAAAGGUCUGCCAAAGACUGACAGAAUAUGGAGUUCAUUUUCACCGAGUGCACCCUGAGAAGAAGUCACAAACAGGAAUAUUGCUUGGAGUCUGUUCUAAAGGUGUCCUUGUGUUUGAAGUUCACAAUGGAGUGCGCACAUUGGUCCUUCGCUUUCCAUGGAGGGAAACCAAGAAAAUAUCUUUUUCUAAAAAGAAAAUCACAUUGCAAAAUACAUCAGAUGGAAUAAAACAUGGCUUCCAGACAGACAACAGUAAGAUAUGCCAGUACCUGCUGCACCUCUGCUCUUACCAGCAUAAGUUCCAGCUACAGAUGAGAGCAAGACAGAGCAACCAAGAUGCCCAAGAUAUUGAGAGAGCUUCGUUUAGGAGCCUGAAUCUCCAAGCAGAGUCUGUUAGAGGAUUUAAUAUGGGACGAGCAAUCAGCACUGGCAGUCUGGCCAGCAGCACCCUCAACAAACUUGCUGUUCGACCUUUAUCAGUUCAAGCUGAGAUUCUGAAGAGGCUAUCCUGCUCAGAGCUGUCGCUUUACCAGCCAUUGCAAAACAGUUCAAAAGAGAAGAAUGACAAAGCUUCAUGGGAGGAAAAGCCUAGAGAGAUGAGUAAAUCAUACCAUGAUCUCAGUCAGGCCUCUCUCUAUCCACAUCGGAAAAAUGUCAUUGUUAACAUGGAACCCCCACCACAAACCGUUGCAGAGUUGGUGGGAAAACCUUCUCACCAGAUGUCAAGAUCUGAUGCAGAAUCUUUGGCAGGAGUGACAAAACUUAAUAAUUCAAAGUCUGUUGCGAGUUUAAAUAGAAGUCCUGAAAGGAGGAAACAUGAAUCAGACUCCUCAUCCAUUGAAGACCCUGGGCAAGCAUAUGUUCUAGGAAUGACUAUGCAUAGUUCUGGAAACUCUUCAUCCCAAGUACCCUUAAAAGAAAAUGAUGUGCUACACAAAAGAUGGAGCAUAGUAUCUUCACCAGAAAGGGAGAUCACCUUAGUGAACCUGAAAAAAGAUGCAAAGUAUGGCUUGGGAUUUCAAAUUAUUGGUGGGGAGAAGAUGGGAAGACUGGACCUAGGCAUAUUUAUCAGUUCAGUUGCCCCUGGAGGACCAGCUGACUUGGAUGGAUGCUUGAAGCCAGGAGACCGUUUGAUAUCUGUGAAUAGUGUGAGUCUGGAGGGAGUCAGCCACCAUGCUGCAAUUGAAAUUUUGCAAAAUGCACCUGAAGAUGUGACACUUGUUAUCUCUCAGCCAAAAGAAAAGAUAUCCAAAGUGCCUUCUACUCCUGUGCAUCUCACCAAUGAGAUGAAAAACUACAUGAAGAAAUCUUCCUACAUGCAAGACAGUGCUAUAGAUUCUUCUUCCAAGGAUCACCACUGGUCACGUGGUACCCUGAGGCACAUCUCGGAGAACUCCUUUGGGCCAUCUGGGGGCCUGCGGGAAGGAAGCCUGAGUUCUCAAGAUUCCAGGACUGAGAGUGCCAGCUUGUCUCAAAGCCAGGUCAAUGGUUUCUUUGCCAGCCAUUUAGGUGACCAAACCUGGCAGGAAUCACAGCAUGGCAGCCCUUCCCCAUCUGUAAUAUCCAAAGCCACCGAGAAAGAGACUUUCACUGAUAGUAACCAAAGCAAAACUAAAAAGCCAGGCAUUUCUGAUGUAACUGAUUACUCAGACCGUGGAGAUUCAGACAUGGAUGAAGCCACUUACUCCAGCAGUCAGGAUCAUCAAACACCAAAACAGGAAUCUUCCUCUUCAGUGAAUACAUCCAACAAGAUGAAUUUUAAAACUUUUUCUUCAUCACCUCCUAAGCCUGGAGAUAUCUUUGAGGUUGAACUGGCUAAAAAUGAUAACAGCUUGGGGAUAAGUGUCACGGUACUGUUUGACAAGGGAGGUGUGAAUACGAGUGUCAGACAUGGUGGCAUUUAUGUGAAAGCUGUUAUUCCCCAGGGAGCAGCAGAGUCUGAUGGUAGAAUUCACAAAGGUGAUCGCGUCCUAGCUGUCAAUGGAGUUAGUCUAGAAGGAGCCACCCAUAAGCAAGCUGUGGAAACACUGAGAAAUACAGGACAGGUGGUUCAUCUGUUAUUAGAAAAGGGACAAUCUCCAACAUCUAAAGAACAUGUCCCGGUAACCCCACAGUGUACCCUUUCAGAUCAGAAUGCCCAAGGUCAAGGCCCAGAAAAAGUGAAGAAAACAACUCAGGUCAAAGACUACAGCUUUGUCACUGAAGAAAAUACAUUUGAGGUAAAAUUAUUUAAAAAUAGCUCAGGUCUAGGAUUCAGUUUUUCUCGAGAAGAUAAUCUUAUACCGGAGCAAAUUAAUGCCAGCAUAGUAAGGGUUAAAAAGCUCUUUCCUGGACAGCCAGCAGCAGAAAGUGGAAAAAUUGAUGUAGGAGAUGUUAUCUUGAAAGUGAAUGGAGCCUCUUUGAAAGGACUAUCUCAGCAGGAAGUCAUAUCUGCUCUCAGGGGAACUGCUCCAGAAGUAUUCUUGCUUCUCUGCAGACCUCCACCUGGUGUGCUACCGGAAAUUGAUACUGCGCUUUUGACCCCACUUCAGUCUCCAGCACAAGUACUUCCAAACAGCAGUAAAGACUCUUCUCAGCCAUCAUGUGUGGAGCAAAGCACCAGCUCAGAUGAAAAUGAAAUGUCAGACAAAAGCAAAAAACAGUGCAAGUCCCCAUCCAGAAGAGACAGUUACAGUGACAGCAGUGGGAGUGGAGAAGAUGACUUAGUGACAGCUCCAGCAAACAUAUCAAAUUCGACCUGGAGUUCAGCUUUGCAUCAGACUCUAAGCAACAUGGUAUCACAGGCACAGAGUCAUCAUGAAGCACCCAAGAGUCAAGAAGAUACCAUUUGUACCAUGUUUUACUAUCCUCAGAAAAUUCCCAAUAAACCAGAGUUUGAGGACAGUAAUCCUUCCCCUCUACCACCGGAUAUGGCUCCUGGGCAGAGUUAUCAACCCCAAUCAGAAUCUGCUUCCUCUAGUUCGAUGGAUAAGUAUCAUAUACAUCACAUUUCUGAACCAACUAGACAAGAAAACUGGACACCUUUGAAAAAUGACUUGGAAAAUCACCUUGAAGACUUUGAACUGGAAGUAGAACUCCUCAUUACCCUAAUUAAAUCAGAAAAAGGAAGCCUGGGUUUUACAGUAACCAAAGGCAAUCAGAGAAUUGGUUGUUAUGUUCAUGAUGUCAUACAGGAUCCAGCCAAAAGUGAUGGAAGGCUAAAACCUGGGGACCGGCUCAUAAAGGUUAAUGAUACAGAUGUUACUAAUAUGACUCAUACAGAUGCAGUUAAUCUGCUCCGGGCUGCAUCCAAAACAGUCAGAUUAGUUAUUGGACGAGUUCUAGAAUUACCCAGAAUACCAAUGUUGCCUCAUUUGCUACCGGACAUAACACUAACGUGCAACAAAGAGGAGUUGGGUUUUUCCUUAUGUGGAGGUCAUGACAGCCUUUAUCAAGUGGUAUAUAUUAGUGAUAUUAAUCCAAGGUCCGUCGCAGCCAUUGAGGGUAAUCUCCAGCUAUUAGAUGUCAUCCAUUAUGUGAACGGAGUCAGCACACAAGGAAUGACCUUGGAGGAAGUUAACAGAGCAUUAGACAUGUCACUUCCUUCAUUGGUAUUGAAAGCAACAAGAAAUGAUCUUCCAGUGGUCCCCAGCUCAAAGAGGUCUGCUGUUUCAGCUCCAAAGUCAACCAAAGGCAAUGGUUCCUACAGUGUGGGGUCUUGCAGCCAGCCUGCCCUCACUCCUAAUGAUUCAUUCUCCACGGUUGCUGGGGAAGAAAUAAAUGAAAUAUCGUACCCCAAAGGAAAAUGUUCUACUUAUCAGAUAAAGGGAUCACCAAACUUGACUCUGCCCAAAGGUAGUUUUCCAAAUCAGUCAUCUAAUUACUCUAAAUGCCCUAAUAAUUCAGAAUCUUAUAUACAAGAAGAUGACAUUUAUGAUGAUUCCCAAGAAGCUGAAGUUAUCCAGUCUCUGCUGGAUGUUGUGGAUGAGGAAGCCCAGAAUCUUUUAAACGAAAAUAAUGCAGCAGGAUACUCCUGUGGUCCAGGUACAUUAAAGAUGAAUGGGAAGUUAUCAGAAGAGAGAACAGAAGAUACAGACUGCGAUGGUUCACCUUUACCUGAGUAUUUUACUGAGGCCACCAAAAUGAAUGGCUGUGAAGAAUAUUGUGAAGAAAAAGUAAAAAGUGAAAGCUUAAUUCAGAAGCCACAAGAAAAGAAGACUGAUGAUGAUGAAAUAACAUGGGGAAAUGAUGAGUUGCCAAUAGAGAGAACAAACCAUGAAGAUUCUGAUAAAGAUCAUUCCUUUCUGACAAACGAUGAGCUCGCUGUACUCCCUGUCGUCAAAGUGCUUCCCUCUGGUAAAUACACGGGUGCCAACUUAAAAUCAGUCAUUCGAGUCCUGCGGGGUUUGCUAGAUCAAGGAAUUCCUUCUAAGGAGCUGGAGAAUCUUCAAGAAUUAAAACCUUUGGAUCAGUGUCUAAUUGGGCAAACUAAGGAAAACAGAAGGAAGAACAGAUAUAAAAAUAUACUUCCCUAUGAUGCUACAAGAGUGCCUCUUGGAGAUGAAGGUGGCUAUAUCAAUGCCAGCUUCAUUAAGAUACCAGUUGGGAAAGAAGAGUUCGUUUACAUUGCCUGCCAAGGACCACUGCCUACAACUGUUGGAGACUUCUGGCAGAUGAUUUGGGAGCAAAAAUCCACAGUGAUAGCCAUGAUGACUCAAGAAGUAGAAGGAGAAAAAAUCAAAUGCCAGCGCUAUUGGCCCAACAUCCUAGGCAAAACAACAAUGGUCAGCAACAGACUUCGACUGGCUCUUGUGAGAAUGCAGCAGCUGAAGGGCUUUGUGGUGAGGGCAAUGACCCUUGAAGAUAUUCAGACCAGAGAGGUGCGCCAUAUUUCUCAUCUGAAUUUCACUGCCUGGCCAGACCAUGAUACACCUUCUCAACCAGAUGAUCUGCUUACUUUUAUCUCCUACAUGAGACACAUCCACAGAUCAGGCCCAAUCAUUACGCACUGCAGUGCUGGCAUUGGACGUUCAGGGACCCUGAUUUGCAUAGAUGUGGUUCUGGGAUUAAUCAGUCAGGAUCUUGAUUUUGACAUCUCUGAUUUGGUGCGCUGCAUGAGACUACAAAGACACGGAAUGGUUCAGACAGAGGAUCAAUAUAUUUUCUGCUAUCAAGUCAUCCUUUAUGUCCUGACACGUCUUCAAGCAGAAGAAGAGCAAAAACAGCAGCCUCAGCUUCUGAAGUGACAUGAAAAGAGCCUCUGGAUGCAUUUCCAUUUCUCUCCUUAACCUCCAGCAGACUCCUGCUCUCUAUCCAAAAUAAAGAUCACAGAGCAGCAAGUUCAUACAACAUGCAUGUUCUCCUCUAUCUUAGAGGGGUAUUCUUCUUGAAAAUAAAAAAUAUUGAAAUGCUGUAUUUUUACAGCUACUUUAACCUAUGAUAAUUAUUUACAAAAUUUUAACACUAACCAAACAAUGCAGAUCUUAGGGAUGAUUAAAGGCAGCAUUUGAUGAUAGCAGACAUUGUUACAAGGACAUGGUGAGUCUAUUUUUAAUGCACCAAUCUUGUUUAUAGCAAAAAUGUUUUCCAAUAUUUUAAUAAAGUAGUUAUUUUAUAGGGGAUACUUGAAACCAGUAUUUAAGCUUUAAAUGACAGUAAUAUUGGCAUAGAAAAAAGUAGCAAAUGUUUACUGUAUCAAUUUCUAAUGUUUACUAUAUAGAAUUUCCUGUAAUAUAUUUAUAUACUUUUUCAUGAAAAUGGAGUUAUCAGUUAUCUGUUUGUUACUGCAUCAUCUGUUUGUAAUCAUUAUCUCACUUUGUAAAUAAAAACACACCUUAAAACAUGAACAAGCCAAAA